GUCCGCACUCUCCGUCCCCGCGGCUGGCGCAGGACCUCACUCGAGCGGAGCGCCCACGGGGAGCGGGUCGCGGGGCGGCGGCGGCGAGGAGGAGGCGAGAAGGAGUUGGAGGAGGAGGAGGAGGAGGCGAGGGCGAGCUAGCCCAGCGGGGUCCCGGCCGCCCCGCGGGCCAAAGUCGAGCCCUCCCGCCCGUGGGCGAGCGCGCCAGCCGCCCCUUCCAGAACAGCCGCCGCCACAAAGAAGAACGGGGGGUGCCGAGGUCCCCAUGACCUCCUAAAGUGGUGCGGUCCCUGCUGAGUGCGCUGCCCGGGCCGUGACCCGCGCCCCUGUGCGUCCCCGCGCGCCUCCGAGCGCCCCUGUGCGCCCCGGCCCGCGCCCCGCCGGCAUGGACGUCCAUACCCGCUGGAAAGCGCGCAGCGCGCUCCGCCCGGGCGCCCCGCUGCUGCCCCCGCUGCUGCUGCUGCUGCUGUGGGCGCCGCCUCCGAGCCGCGCAGCUCAGCCAGCAGAUCUCCUGAAGGUUCUAGAUUUUCACAACUUGCCUGAUGGAAUAACAAAGACAACAGGCUUUUGCGCCACGCGGCGAUCUUCCAAAGGCCCGGAUGUCGCUUACAGAGUCACCAAAGACGCGCAGCUCAGCGCACCCACCAAGCAGCUGUACCCUGCGUCUGCAUUUCCCGAGGACUUCUCCAUCCUAACAACUGUGAAAGCCAAGAAAGGCAGCCAGGCCUUCCUGGUCUCCAUCUACAACGAGCAGGGUAUCCAGCAGAUUGGGCUGGAGCUGGGCCGCUCUCCCGUCUUCCUCUACGAGGACCACACGGGGAAGCCUGGCCCGGAAGACUACCCCCUCUUCCGGGGCAUCAACCUGUCAGAUGGCAAGUGGCACAGAAUUGCUCUCAGCGUCCACAAGAAAAAUGUCACCUUGAUCCUCGACUGUAAAAAGAAGACCACCAAAUUCCUCGACCGCAGCGACCACCCCAUGAUCGACAUCAAUGGCAUCAUCGUGUUUGGCACCCGGAUCCUGGAUGAGGAGGUGUUUGAGGGUGACAUCCAGCAGCUGCUCUUUGUCUCGGACCACCGGGCAGCUUAUGAUUACUGUGAGCACUACAGCCCUGACUGUGACACCGCAGUACCUGACACCCCACAGUCGCAGGACCCCAAUCCAGAUGAAUAUUACACGGAAGGAGACGGCGAGGGUGAGACCUAUUACUACGAAUACCCCUACUACGAAGACCCCGAAGACCUAGGGAAGGAGCCCACCCCCAGCAAGAAGCCCGUGGAAGCUGCCAAAGAAACCACAGAGGUCCCCGAGGAGCUGACCCCGACCCCCACGGAAGCUGCUCCCAUGCCUGAAACCAGUGAAGGGGCUGGGAAGGAAGAGGACGUCGGCAUCGGGGACUAUGACUACGUGCCCAGUGAGGACUACUACACGCCCUCACCGUAUGAUGACCUCACCUAUGGCGAGGGGGAGGAGAACCCCGACCAGCCCACAGACCCAGGCGCUGGGGCCGAAAUUCCCACCAGCACCGCCGACACCUCCAACUCCUCCAAUCCAGCUCCGCCUCCAGGGGAAGGUGCGGAUGACUUGGAGGGGGAGUUCACUGAGGAAACGAUCCGGAACCUUGACGAGAACUACUACGACCCCUACUACGACCCCACCAGCUCCCCGUCGGAGAUCGGGCCGGGAAUGCCGGCGAACCAGGAUACCAUCUAUGAAGGGAUUGGAGGACCUCGGGGCGAGAAAGGCCAAAAGGGAGAACCAGCGAUUAUCGAGCCGGGCAUGCUCAUCGAGGGCCCGCCUGGCCCAGAAGGCCCCGCGGGUCUUCCCGGACCUCCAGGAACCAUGGGUCCCACUGGCCAAGUCGGGGACCCUGGAGAAAGGGGCCCCCCUGGACGCCCAGGCCUUCCUGGGGCCGAUGGCCUGCCCGGUCCUCCAGGAACCAUGCUCAUGCUGCCCUUCCGGUUUGGAGGUGGCGGCGAUGCGGGCUCCAAAGGCCCCAUGGUCUCAGCCCAGGAGUCCCAGGCGCAAGCCAUUCUCCAGCAGGCCAGGUUGGCACUGAGGGGACCAGCUGGCCCGAUGGGUCUCACAGGGAGACCUGGCCCUGUGGGUCCCCCUGGGAGCGGAGGUUUGAAGGGCGAGCCGGGAGACGUGGGGCCUCAGGGUCCUCGAGGUGUGCAAGGCCCGCCUGGUCCGGCCGGGAAGCCCGGAAGACGGGGUCGGGCUGGGAGUGAUGGAGCCAGAGGAAUGCCUGGACAAACUGGCCCCAAGGGUGACCGGGGUUUCGACGGCCUGGCUGGGUUGCCAGGCGAGAAGGGCCACAGGGGUGACCCUGGUCCUUCCGGCCCACCAGGACCUCCGGGAGACGAUGGAGAAAGGGGUGACGACGGAGAAGUUGGGCCCAGGGGGCUGCCUGGGGAGCCCGGGCCACGUGGUCUGCUUGGGCCGAAGGGGCCCCCAGGUCCUCCCGGACCUCCCGGUGUCACGGGUAUGGACGGCCAGCCGGGGCCAAAAGGAAAUGUGGGUCCCCAGGGAGAGCCUGGCCCCCCAGGACAGCAGGGUAAUCCAGGCGCCCAGGGUCUUCCAGGCCCCCAGGGUGCAAUUGGUCCUCCAGGAGAAAAGGGUCCCUUGGGGAAACCAGGCCUUCCAGGAAUGCCCGGUGCUGACGGACCCCCGGGACACCCUGGCAAAGAAGGCCCUCCAGGAGAGAAAGGAGGUCAGGGUCCACCUGGCCCCCAGGGUCCGAUUGGCUACCCAGGUCCUCGAGGAGUCAAGGGGGCCGAUGGCAUCCGUGGUCUGAAGGGCACAAAGGGCGAGAAGGGUGAAGACGGCUUUCCUGGGUUUAAAGGAGACAUGGGCAUCAAGGGUGAUCGGGGGGAGAUCGGCCCACCCGGUCCCAGGGGAGAAGAUGGCCCUGAAGGCCCAAAGGGUCGCGGAGGUCCCAAUGGUGACCCCGGUCCUCUGGGACCCCCUGGGGAGAAGGGAAAACUCGGAGUCCCAGGGUUACCAGGGUAUCCAGGAAGACAAGGACCAAAGGGCUCUAUUGGAUUCCCUGGAUUUCCUGGCGCCAAUGGAGAGAAGGGCGGCAGGGGGACCCCUGGAAAGCCAGGACCGCGGGGGCAGCGAGGCCCAACGGGUCCGAGGGGUGAAAGAGGCCCCCGGGGCAUCACUGGGAAGCCUGGCCCCAAGGGCAACUCCGGAGGUGACGGCCCAGCUGGCCCUCCUGGUGAACGGGGACCCAAUGGACCCCAAGGACCCACAGGAUUUCCUGGACCAAAGGGCCCCCCUGGCCCUCCAGGCAAGGAUGGACUCCCAGGACACCCUGGACAGAGAGGCGAGACUGGUUUCCAAGGCAAGACCGGCCCUCCAGGCCCCCCCGGCGUGGUCGGCCCUCAGGGUCCCACGGGAGAAACGGGCCCAAUGGGUGAGCGUGGCCACCCUGGGCCCCCUGGACCCCCCGGUGAACAGGGGCUUCCGGGCCUUGCUGGAAAAGAAGGGACGAAGGGUGACCCAGGCCCUGCAGGCCUCCCUGGGAAAGAUGGCCCUCCAGGAUUACGUGGUUUCCCUGGGGACCGAGGGCUUCCUGGUCCAGUGGGAGCUCUUGGACUGAAAGGCAAUGAAGGGCCCCCUGGCCCACCAGGCCCUGCGGGAUCUCCAGGGGAGAGAGGUCCAGCUGGAGCCGCUGGGCCCAUCGGAAUUCCAGGGAGACCUGGGCCCCAGGGACCCCCAGGGCCGGCAGGAGAGAAAGGGGCUCCUGGCGAGAAAGGCCCACAAGGCCCAGCUGGCCGAGACGGUCUCCAGGGGCCUGUGGGGCUCCCGGGUCCAGCUGGCCCUGUGGGUCCCCCUGGAGAAGACGGAGAUAAGGGAGAGAUCGGGGAGCCGGGGCAGAAAGGAAGCAAGGGGGACAAAGGAGAACAGGGUCCUCCUGGGCCUACAGGUCCUCAAGGCCCCAUCGGACAGCCAGGCCCCUCUGGAGCUGACGGCGAGCCGGGGCCUCGGGGCCAGCAGGGCCUUUUCGGGCAGAAAGGUGAUGAAGGUCCCAGAGGCUUUCCUGGACCCCCUGGGCCAGUGGGGCUGCAGGGUUUGCCAGGACCUCCAGGCGAGAAGGGUGAGACAGGAGACGUGGGCCAGAUGGGCCCCCCGGGUCCCCCUGGCCCCCGAGGACCCUCCGGAGCUCCAGGUGCUGAUGGCCCACAAGGUCCCCCAGGUGGAAUAGGAAACCCUGGUGCAGUGGGAGAGAAGGGCGAGCCUGGCGAAGCAGGUGAGCCUGGCCUUCCGGGAGAAGGCGGCCCCCCGGGACCCAAAGGAGAAAGGGGAGAGAAGGGCGAGUCAGGCCCUUCAGGUGCUGCCGGACCCCCUGGACCCAAAGGCCCUCCCGGAGAUGAUGGUCCCAAAGGCAGCCCUGGCCCAGUGGGUUUUCCUGGAGAUCCUGGCCCCCCCGGAGAGCCUGGCCCCGCGGGUCAAGAUGGUCCCCCUGGUGACAAAGGAGAUGAUGGUGAACCCGGGCAGACGGGAUCCCCCGGCCCUACUGGUGAACCAGGUCCAUCGGGGCCUCCAGGAAAAAGGGGUCCCCCAGGCCCCGCAGGCCCCGAAGGCAGACAGGGAGAGAAAGGGGCCAAGGGAGAAGCCGGCUUGGAAGGCCCUCCUGGGAAGACUGGCCCCAUCGGCCCCCAGGGGGCCCCUGGGAAGCCCGGACCGGAUGGCCUUCGAGGGAUCCCUGGCCCUGUGGGAGAACAAGGUCUCCCAGGAUCCCCAGGCCCGGACGGUCCCCCCGGCCCCAUGGGUCCCCCAGGACUUCCCGGCCUCAAAGGAGAUUCUGGUCCCAAAGGUGAAAAGGGUCAUCCAGGCCUGAUCGGGCUCAUCGGUCCUCCGGGUGAACAGGGUGAGAAGGGCGACCGUGGUCUCCCUGGCCCCCAGGGCUCCUCCGGUCCUAAGGGAGAACAGGGUAUCACUGGUCCUUCUGGCCCGAUUGGGCCUCCUGGGCCCCCUGGCCUGCCGGGUCCGCCUGGUCCAAAAGGUGCUAAGGGCUCCUCGGGUCCAACUGGCCCGAAGGGUGAGGCAGGCCACCCAGGACCCCCAGGCCCCCCGGGCCCCCCGGGAGAGGUCAUCCAGCCCCUGCCAAUCCAGGCAUCCAGGACGCGGCGGAACAUCGACGCCAGCCAGCUGCUGGACGACGGGAAUGGCGAGAACUACGUGGACUACGCGGACGGCAUGGAAGAGAUCUUCGGCUCUCUCAACUCUCUGAAGCUGGAGAUUGAGCAGAUGAAACGGCCCCUGGGCACGCAGCAGAACCCCGCCCGCACCUGCAAGGACCUGCAGCUCUGCCACCCCGACUUCCCAGAUGGUGAAUACUGGGUCGAUCCUAACCAAGGAUGCUCCAGGGAUUCCUUCAAGGUUUACUGCAACUUCACAGCCGGGGGGUCGACAUGCGUCUUCCCUGACAAGAAGUCCGAAGGGGCCAGAAUCACUUCUUGGCCCAAAGAAAACCCGGGCUCCUGGUUCAGUGAAUUCAAGCGUGGGAAACUGCUCUCCUAUGUGGACGCCGAGGGCAACCCUGUGGGUGUGGUACAGAUGACCUUCCUGCGGCUGCUGAGCGCCUCUGCCCACCAGAACGUCACCUACCACUGCUACCAGUCAGUGGCCUGGCAGGACGCAGCCACGGGCAGCUACGACAAGGCCCUCCGCUUCCUGGGCUCCAACGACGAGGAGAUGUCCUAUGACAACAACCCCUACAUCCGCGCCCUGGUGGACGGCUGUGCUACCAAGAAAGGCUACCAGAAGACGGUUCUGGAGAUCGACACCCCCAAAGUGGAGCAGGUGCCCAUCGUGGACAUCAUGUUCAAUGACUUCGGUGAAGCGUCACAGAAAUUUGGAUUUGAAGUGGGGCCGGCUUGCUUCAUGGGCUAGGAGCCGCCGAGCCCGGGCUCCCGAGAGCAACCUCGUGACCUCAGCAUGCCAUUCGUUCGUGAGUGUCCCGUGCACGUCCUGACCCUGGACAGUGAAGGCUUCUCCCUCCCCUCCCACCUGACUUCAUCUACGCCUCGGCACCACGGGGUGUGGGACCCCAGCCCGGAGAGAACAGAGGGAAGGAGCCGCGCCCCCACCUGGAGCUGAAUCACAUGACCUAGCUGCACCCCAGCGCCUGGGCCCGCCCCACGCUCUGUCCACACCCACGCGCCCCGGGAGCGGGGCCAUGCCUCCAGCCCCCCAGCUCGCCCGACCCAUCCUGUUCGUGAAUAGGUCUCAGGGGUUGGGGGAGGGACUGCCAGAUUUGGACACUAUAUUUUUUUCUAAAUUCAACUUGAAGAUGUGUAUUUCCCCUGACCUUCAAAAAAUGUUCCAAGGUAAGCCUCGUAAAGGUCAUCCCACCAUCACCAAAGCCUCCGUUUUUAACAACCUCCAACACGAUCCAUUUAGAGGCCAAAUGUCAUUCUGCAGGUGCCUUCCCGAUGGAUUAAAGGUGCUUAUGUUUUUGUGAGUUUUAAGUAAAUAUUUGUAUUGUAUUGUUAUAAAUGUUAAGUGUGCCUGGCUUUCAAUCAUGCACGGAAACCCAGUCUCAGUCCCACGGACAGAAUGGGCGAGGCAUGGAUUCUGGGUUGCAGUACCGUUCUGAUUAGAAAUAGGAAGUCUCCCCACCCCCGCCCUGGCCAAGAACGUGCAAUAAAUUGGAAGUUUGCCCCGGGGCAGCAAGAAUUUAUGCUGCCAUUGAAAAGCAGGUACCAGUGCCCCUUUUCAGACAGUUUUUGAUUCGCUCUAGACUUUUUUUUUUUUUAAUAGGGAAAAAAUUUGAUAAUUUUCUUUUUUCUACAUGCACUUAAGACUAAAACACAGGUUUGGAUUAAUUUUAUUUGCUUCCUUUUUCCGCUUUUCUUCCCGCAGAGCCUGAUGGGAGAAUGUCCAGGGCAGGGAAACCACAUUUUUUGUAGGUGAUAACUCAAUGAAAAUUGGUGCUUAUUUUUUACACUUCUCUCUUGUGGCUCUCUUGUGGUGCUAUCUAUCUGUUUUAAGGUCUCCUUGAAGGCGCACUGGGGACCCUGGCCAUGCCUCGUUCUCCCUGCUUUCUUUAUCCUGUUAUUGCCUCCACAGUCUGUUGCCAAGGACUCUAAGAUCAAUGCACGUCACUUUCCUUUCCACUGGGCAGGAUAGCCAAGCACACUCCCUCCUGCGCUCUCCCGCCCCGGUGCGUCCACUCCCGAGGGCUGUUAUGAGGACUGGGUUGUGCCUACUUGAUUUGAAAACACACACAAGCAAUAAAAAGCCUCUUCCUGCAUUGUCUGUGGUGUGACCAUAGCAGAUUAUAUUUGGUUCCUGAAUGUUUGUGGUGCUAAUUUCUGUGUUUGUUCCAAGCCGUUCAGUCAUGCCAUGCGCUGCCUCGGUAGAUGGAGUAAUGUACAAUGAACUCCAUGAGUCUCUCCAGGGCUGCCUGCAGCACGUCUUUUCCAAGUAGCCUAUUUGGAUUCCCAUCUCAAAUGUCCUGGAUGCGAGCGUCAGCGGCUCCAGAGCUCGGGGCGGGUGAGGUCCCCUUUGGGGAACCCUUUCCUGGCCAUCGAGGUCGGGGGGCUGCCGUCUGUGGGCAGGAGGACCCGAGGGGCAGCCAGGAAAGGCGAUCUCUUCACUGUGAAAAGUUGCCCGGGUGCAGCGCCUUUUCCUUCUACCAUGGGAAAUGCAGGCUGGGCCCUUGGGGUGAGCCUGCGGGGCUCUGGUGCUGUCCCCGACCCCCACCACCACCAGAAUGCAGUUCCAGCUUAGGAAGCCACAAACAAGCCACCCAGGAGGAACAAAACACCGCCAGCGUGGAUUUUCCAAAUUUCCCUGGAAAGUAAGUCUCGCUCUUGCCAAAGAAAAGUCUGGCUUGGAGAGUCUCUGGAGCCCAGGAUGCCAGCAUGUGCCAAUGACUGUCACCUUCAUCUCUUCAAAAGAAAAGCCAUAGCCGAGGACUGUCCCGCGACCCCCGUGGACUGCGUCUAGGUCAUGUGAUUCUGUUUUCAUUUCUCAUCCCAUCCAAUUUGUCCUUUUCUCCUGUCAUUUUCUUCCUCUGUGGUCCCUUCAAAGUUGUUAUAAUUUGUACUGAACUUCAAAAUGUGUCCCGUUCUCCCCAGACCACUCUAGCCACAGUAUAUUGCAAUAAAAUUACUUCUUAUAUUUGCAGAAAUUCUUUUGGUGUAAUUUUAUUUUUUCCUCUCAAUAUAUAUAAUUGGACAAACGCUGGCAAAAAGAAAAAAAUGGUAAGCAAAAAACCCAAGAUAAAGUUUCGAGGACAUCAGGCCUUUUGAAAUACAAUGUCAAAUGACACAUUGUACGGUUUCAAAAAAUCCGCUAGACAUGUCAUAAGUUUUAACUGUAAUGCCCAGGAAAGGAUAUCUUAAAAUAUUCUAAACUUGUGUAACAAAGGAAUAAUUAACUGUAAUAGUUUUUCAAUAAAUCGAGUUGGGUGUUUCCACCGUAAA